CCCACAUUCCUUUCUUCUGUUUAUUCAUUUGACAGAUACCUACUGAGUUCCCGCUCUGUGUGAGGUCGGGGGUGGAGUCUGGGGAGAAGGAAAUAAGCCAGGAACCUGCGUUUGCCGAUGUGAUGGUGUGAAGUGGUGACUGGCCUGAGGGCCCCUCCUUAUGGGAUUAGUGCCCCCAGAAAGAGCCUUAUCGGGGGUCUGUCCCUCCCGCCAUUGCCUCCUGAGGACCCGCAUUUCUCCCUCCAGGGGACACUGCACGCCAGGCACCGUCUUGGGUAGAGAGCAGCCCUCACCAAAUGCGGGUGCCUUGGCCUUGGACUUUCAGCCCCCAGCACUGUGAGAAGUUCUCUCUCCUUUGGGACCAAGGUGGAGUCUUGCUUCUCCGUGGGCAUGUGAGGGUGAGUGAAACCACGACACUUCUCUGCAUGGUGCUCGUCUGUGUUCUCCGGAGAGGCCGCUACUUGCCGGGGCCCUACAAUCAGGACGAUGAUGACGGAUGCCGGCUCCCACCAGCGAGGUCACGUGUCCAGGCCGUGAUGUCGUGAAGGCUGGGAGAUGCUGGCACCGCUCACCGGGGUGGUAAACUCUCUGCUGCAACAGGUGAGGGGCUGGGCUGAGCGCAGGAAGGGGACCCCGAGGAUGGGGCUUGCCUUGGGCUGGCGCUGGGGGCUCGGGCUGUGUCUGCAGAGCCACAGCACGGGGUCAGUAAACGGGGCCCACUCUGAGCCGACCCUCCGCUCCUACCGCAGUGAAGCUGGGGGCCUGGCUGCCUUGACUGUAACGUGCUGGAAUCCACACAGCCCCUUUAAGAGAGAAAAAUGCUGACUUCCACCUGGCGGGCUCAUAGGCCAGCCUCGCUCACUGCAGUCACCUGUGGGUGUUUCACACACUGGGGGUGCGGCCGCCUCGUGGAGCAAGUCUGUCGAUGCCACUUUUCCAACAGCCAGUGCUCACGUCGCCACGGGUCAUGAUUUGGUAGCUCUUGCAGUUUCAAACAUGUUCCUUUUCUUUUUUUUUUUUUUGAGACGGAGUUUCGGUCUUGGUGCCCAGGCUGGAGUGCGGUGGCGCGAUCUCAGCUCACUGCAACCUCUGCCUCCCGGGUUCAAGUGAUUCUCCUGCCUCAGCCUCCCAAGUAACUGGGAUUACAGGCACCCACCACCCCGCCUGGCUAAUUUUUGUGUUUCUAGUAGAGACAGGGUUUCACCGUGUUGGCCAGGCUGGUCUCGAACUCCUGAGCUCAUGAGAUCCGCCCACCUCGGCCUCCCAAAGUGCUGGGAUUACAGGCGUGAGGCACUGCGCCCGGCCAGAACAUUUCCAUCUUUAUUAUAUCUGUUCGGUGAUCUGUGAUCAGUGAGUUUUGAUAUUAGUAUGAUCAUUGUUUUGGGGCACCACAAACUGUCCCCAUAUAAGACAGGAAGCUUAAUCCAUCCAUGUUGUGUGUUCCGACUGCUCCACCGACCAGCAGCUUCCCCAUCCCUCUCCCUCUCCUCAGGCCUGUCUAGUCCCUGAGACACAGAGCACUGAAGUCAGGCCACGUGAUACCCUCCAGUGGCCUCGGAUGUUCAAAUGGUAGGAAGGGUUGCAGGUCUCUCCUUCAAAUCAGAAGUUAGGAAUGGCUAAGCCUGGUGAGAAGGGCAUGCCAAAAUCUGGACAGACGGAAAGCCAGGCCUCUUGUGCAAAAGAGUUAGCCAAGUUUUGAGUAUAAAGGAAAAGUCCUUGAAGGAAAGUGUAAGUGCUACUCCAGUGGACACACGAUUGGGAAGGAAGCGAAAAGGCUGUUGCCAAUGUGGAAAACGUGGUGGCGGUCGGAUAGAAGAUCAAACCAGCCACGACGUCUCCUCAAGCCACAGCCGGAUCCAGACCAAGGCUGUAACUCUCCUCAAUUCUGUGGAGGCUGAGAGAGGUGAGGAAGCUCCAGAAGAAAAGCUGGCAGCUGGCAGAGGUGGCUUCCUGAGGUUUAGGGACAGAAGCCACCUCCAUCACACAGAAGUGCAGGUGAGGCAGCACGUCCAGCUCCCCGAUGGAAGAUCCAGCUGAGAUCACGGAUGAAGGCGGCUACACUCACAGCAGAUCUUCAGUGUAGAUGAAACAGCAGCAACAGUGACAGCAGCAACAGGGCACAGGCCAUCUCUAGAACUUUCUGGAACAGGACACGCAAACUGAGCCCCGUUGCCCCUGUUGUACCAAUGAGGACGGAGGCUGCAGAGUGGGCGGGCGUGGCCUGGGUCAGAACCAGCCCCGUGGCUGCACCCGUGGGUGCACGAGCUUCGCAGCCAGCUGCCAGGGCGCUUUGGCUCAGCACGGCCCUGGUGACCCCAGGCAUGGUGCCGAUGUCACCCCAGGCAUGGCGCCGACGUCACCUCAGGGUCAACUCAUGCCUGACGGCCCCGGGAUGUGGUGAUGGGGUCUCAGCUGCGCACCUGUGGGCGCCACCUGCAGUUCCUUCUGCCGUCCCCGUCUUUCCCUGGGCUCUGGGCACCCUGGGAGAAUGCCCGUUCCAUCUCCAGGGACUGCUCUGGCCUCGGAGAUACUGUCGCCCAGUGACUCUCAAGUCAGAAACCACAGGCCGACGCCCUGCUUGCUGGGCUGUGCCGCAGCCUUGGUCUGAUUCCAGGUGUGUCCCUGCCCAGGGCUGUCUGCCUGCCACUGCCUCUGCCCAGGCCAGGACAACGGGGGCAGCUCAGGGGUCCCUCCAGCACCUGACCAGGGUGAUGGGGAGACCCUCUGCAGGUGCAGGGGCCCAUGAGCUCCCACCCCAGCCUGCCACACCCGCGGGGGAAGCACCUGCCCUGGUAAGCAGCGCCUGCCUGGGGCCCUGGGAGCAGACCCGGGGGGAGGGGCUGUGCCGAGGCCACGUGCAGAUGCCAGGGCUUGCCAUGGCAACCAAGGACAGGCAUCCUCGGCUGGCCAGGCGAGGGCGUGUCCUUUCCAGCUCCCCGAUCUUACAUUCUUUCCCUGCACCCACCAUAUGCACACAUGCACACAGACAUCUACUCUGUACACCAAACAUGCAGACACGCCAAGAUAAGCAUGAACAUACAGGCACAUGUAACCUUGGCAAACACACACACAUGCCUACCAGGCACGCCGCAGACCCCGACACCAUCACACACAGGCCCUCAAGUCACAUGCGGUUAUGUUUCCAGCCUCCUGUGCAGACAGGCAUACGUGCACAGCCCCACCCGCCUCUGCGUGUCCACGAGCAGACGCGCACCUGUGCGGAUCCAGACACGCGUGCACCUUGUGGAUAAGCAGACGUGCGUCUCUCUGGACGUGCGUGCUCAUGGGCACGUGCGUCUGCAUUCAGAUCUGUGUACACAUCGCACCCUGAGUACCCACAGACACGCGUGAGCUCUCAGGUGUGCACACGCGAAGGCACGGCUCGCGGCUUCUGCGGAGGCCUUUCUGAUGGAUGGAACAGGUCCUCACUGUUCUGGACAGGAGUGGGAGGGCAAGAGGCCCAGCCUUACACAGUCAGUUAAACGCCGUCGGCAGGGCUCCCCACGGCAGGGGCGGGGGUGGAGGGAAGAUGCGGAGGUGGUGCACUGGAAGAAAGGCUCCAAACAGCUGCAGCCCAGUCCCUCUCGGGGCCCCACUUGGCAGCGUCUCCUGCAGGGCCUCUGAGCUGCUGGUUUUGGAAAUGCAGCCAAUGCUGAGGUCCCUCAGCAGCCCAGCAGCAGGCCAGGAGGGCUACGGAGCUGCCAGGGGCUUCCAGGACAGCUCUGGGAGGGCCAGGGAGCUGCUAGGGGCCUCCAGCAGCAGGCAGGGAGGGCUGCGGAGCCGCCGGGGGCCUCCAGGACAGCUGUGCCCUGUGGUUGGCCUUCUGUCUUUGGGCCUCUGUGCUGGGCAUCUUGGAGAAACCAGCUGUGGCUGUGUGUGCUCAGGGCUGGUCAGGGGCCCCACGUCCCACCCCCUCUGGUGCCCCUAAUUUUAGGAAAACCCAUGAGAAACUACCAUCUCUACUGAGCACAGAACGUGCUUUCUAGAAGAUUCCAACCCAGGAGUCUCGUUAGGAGGUAGCGGGCCUGCAGCAGGAGGAUUUUCUUUCGGUGUAAUUUAAAAAUUAACUUUUCCAUCCCUCUGAGAAUCUAGAGUAGCAAGUUCUUGAGGGAACGGGACAGGCAGCGGCCAAUGCUCACAGGCCUCUGCUGCACGCUAGUGACGAAACGCAGCGGAACGCGUGCUCCCAGCCUGGGGCCAGGAGUCUGGAGUCAGGCAUCGUGGGGCCGAGGCUCCAGGGGAGGAUCCUGCCACCCGGUCUGGCCUCUGCUGGCACCCAGGUGCUGGCUGUGGCUGCAGCGCUGCAGUCUCUGCCUCCUUCCCUUGCGUCUCCUCCUUGUCUCUGUUUUCUCUUCUUAUAAGGAUGCCUGUGUUUGGAUUUAGGGUCUACCCUCAUCAGCUGGGCCUCAUCUUAACCAACUCCACCUGCAAAGGCCCUGUUUCCAGAUGAGGCCGCAGCCUGAGGUUCUGGGUGGACACCAUUCUACCCAGUACCACGUAUGUACAUACUCACGGAACCCUCCAACGCUCCUAAGAGAGGGGCCCCUGAUGGUCCCCAGUUUACAGGCGUGAAAGUUCCAGGAGGAGGCUGAGCUGCACAGGGUCACUGGGUGCUGGGCACUUGCCCCCGUCGCCAGCUGCUGCCCAGAAACCACCCCCACACUUUGUGACCUGCAGCAACACCAGGGAUGAUUUUUAUCCUGAAUCCACAGCUCGGGCAGGUUUGCUGCGGACGGCUUGUUUCUGCUACACUUGGCAGGAGCUGGGGCUGCCCACACGCUGGGGGCCGAGUUCGCCCAACGCUCAGGCACCUGGUGGGUCGUGGUGGCUGUCGGCUGAGCCCUGGCCAGGCUGUGACCAGACACCUGCAGGGGCUCCUCUGUGUGGUCUGGGCUCCCACACAGCCUGGCAGCUGGUUCCAUGAGUAAGAGCCCAGAGCCCCCAGCCCAGAGCCCAGAGCCCGGAGCAGGCCAAGUGGGCCGGCUGCAGCCUUCUGCCCUGUGCUCCUCCCCAGCCCGCCAUGAAGGCCGUGCAUUCAGGCAGCGGGGAGCGGGGCUCCUCUCCACGGGGGGGUUGAGGGGGAAGGCAAAGGUCUGGAAGAACACGCAGGACUGAAAAUAUUGUUUCGGCCAUGUGUGCAUUUUUGGCACAAUCUACCAUAUUAGUAGACGCCAGUUCCAAACCUGGAAACUUGAGCCUCUGGACCUAGGUCUCUGGAUCCUCAGCACGGACCAAGCCGCAUCUGGGGAGCGCCUGCCGGGGAGCCAAGCCCGCAGGAGGGGCAGGUGCUGGCGGGGGCCGUCACUGCAGUCCUCAUAUGGUUAGGCCGGGGAAUGAUAUUUCCUCUCCACCUCUCUCGGUGGACCCUAAAUCCAAGAGAGAAGACAUCUUUCUCACGGCAGCCCCAUCUCAGGCAGAUCCUGUCGUUUGCAGCCUCUGACCUGUGGGAGGAGCCCAGGCCUGCCGGGAGGCGGGUGCACACUCACAGAACGUGCAGCGCAGGUGUGCACUCUAGAGCCCACCUCAGUGCUGAGGUCGACGUCACCCCCGGGCUCUUGGGCCGUGGCCAACGGCAGGUAUGUUGCAAAUCUGAACAGCAUGGUGUUUCUAAAUGUGGGACCUUUGCCCCCAAAUCCAGACUUCCGGCUUUUCUUUUUUCUAUUUUUUUUUUUUUUUGAGACGGAGUGUCGCUCUGUCGCCCAGGCUGGAGUGCAGUGGCGCGAUCUCAGCUCACUGUAAGCUCCACCUCCCAGGUUCACGCCAUUCUCCUGCCUCAACCUCCUGAGUAGCUGGGACUACAGGCGCCCGCCACUACGCCCGGCUAAUUAUUUGUAUUUUUAGUAGAGACGGGGGUUUCACCGUGUUAGCCAGGAUGGUCUCGAUCUCCUGACCUCGUGAUCCGCCCACCUCGGCCUCCCAAAGUGCUGGGAUUACAGGCGUGAGCCGCUGCGCCCGGCCCCAGCUUUUCUUUAAAAGAACAGAAGGUGGAGCAAGGCUGAGUCCACACCCUGCGAGUCAGGAAGUAGCUGCAGCUGUCUGCGGGCCGCCGCCUCGCCCCGCGGGCUCCUGCCUGCUGUGCCACGCCCCUCACUGCUCCCCACCGCGUUGCAGCUGGCGCUCCACCUGCCGCUCACCAGACCAGGGCUGGCAGCCCCUUCCCAGACCUGCCUCUCUGUGAUCUCAUGUGACCAUGGCAGCUGCAGCUGUCUGUGGGCUGCACACCCGGGCACGGUGGCAAGCUCCCGGGAUGGGGGAUGAUGAGCAACCCUCAGAUGGCCCCACAGUGUGCCAGGUAUCGCCCUUACACACCUGUAAGGGCGUCACCUCAUUUCAUUCUCAUGACAGCUCUCUGGGGGGGGGCAUCAUCACUAUCACCUUACAGAUAAGGAAGCUCAGGCACCAAGAGGUUAGAUAACUUGCUCCAGGUCACAUAGGGACGAUGAGCGUUGCAGGUGUGUGCAGGUGUGCAUAGGUGUGUUCCAGUGUGUGCAGGUAUGCCCAUGUGUGUGCAGGUGUGCUCCAGUGUGUGCAGGUGUGCUCAGGUGUGCGCAGAGGUUCCCAGGUGUGUGCAGGUGUGCCCAGGUGUGUGCCGAUGUGCCUAGGUGUCUGCAGGUGUGCUCAGGUGUGUUGAGUGCCAGGCACGAGGAGCCGAGGCCCUUCCACAUGUCUUACCCCAGGCUCCAGCGGCCCAGUUCCAGGGUGGGAGGUCUGCCAAGGCCUCAUGGCCGCCUGCUCAGGAUGGGGGAGGGCACCUUCCCCUUCUUGGCCAUCUGCCCAGUCCUCUCGGGGUUGGGGGCUGUGCUGGAGGGGGCGGGCAAGGACGUGCCUACGCUGUCAUCUGGUGGCUGCCUCCCAGGAACUAGGGAAUUCCAGGUUCCUGUCCAGAGUCCACCCGCAGGCUCCUGACACCAGUGGCUCCCCCAGGCCCAGAGGACGCAGGCUGCUGAGGGGCUGCAGCCCAUCAGGGUCCCUGCCUGAGCCCCGCUGUCAGGCAGGCAUCCCACAGGAGCACCCUGGGCUCUGCUGCCUUCCCGCGGUUUCCUGUUGUGGGCAGGGCCACAGGGGCUGUUGGGGAAAUUCAAGGCCUGGGACCUGGGAACUUCCAGCCUGGGGAGGGAGACGGGCGAGGGCCAGGAGCGGGUUUCAGGAAGUGACCAGUGCCCUGGGAGAGGGAGAGUGGCCGCAGGUGGCUGCUUCCCACAGGCCCCAUGGAAAGGACAUCUGAGCUGAGGCCUGAGGAUGGGAGAACCCUCAUGUGUGAAAAUGGGGAAGUGGGCGGGAGGUGGGGAGGUGGGCAAGUCGGCAAGUCACAGGGCGUGGGGUAGGAGCUUGAGCGUCACCGUCGGGAAGAGGCCGUGUGGUCAGGGAGGGAGGAGGGUGGCUGCCGUUGGCAGCUGUCAGAUGGGACUCGCAGGCAGGUUUCGGACAGGUUUCCUUUCCCAGGCCAUCUGCGAGAACAGAGACGAGGGCUUGGAUCAGUUUCUGUCUGAGUUGGCGCCUUCCCAGGCUGGCUGUUGGCUCUGCUCCCUUCUGGGACCUGUUGGGAUGAGCAGAUCAGGGAGUAUUUUGAGCCGAAAGGUACGUGGGGAAACUGGGACUGACAGCGAAUUCCCUGUCUGCGUUUGCCCACAUGAGUUUUUCUUUGUGCUCUUGUGCUCUCAGGAAUUCAGCCUCUGAAUCCCUCCUGGGCCUGGGGUGGAGCAGGGUGAACACAUACGGAAGCGUAAACACAGCGGGCCGACUUCAGCCUGCAGCUCAGCCCUGCGGUCUCCUGGGCAACGCGCUGCGUGGGGACAUUGUCUCUCACCUGAAAAGCUGCUUACGGGCCCCCACCUCGUCGUGGGUUUAAAGCGGAUUAAUGGGAGGGUUGGUGGUUCUGGGGCUGGCAGGGCUUCCCAGCAGGGGCAGCCCCUUCAUGUGGUGGCGAGCUUGGUAGUGACAACAGGCAGGCCGCUGUGCCCCGGGUGGGUGGCUGGAGCUGGGCGUGGGGUGUCUCCCCGUGAGGACUGUCUGCCCUGCCCGCUGCUCACAAGCCUUCUGCGUUUCCCACCACGCUCUCCUCACCUUCUACUGGGAGGAAGGUCCCAGGGCACGGGAGGGACCCUGUCUAGAGUGGAGCUGGGCUGCCCCAUCUCAGGUCAUGGGUCACGGCUGCCCCAUCUCAGGUGACGGCAGCCCCCUUCAGGUGAAGGCCAAGGCGCGGCUCUUCUCCUCCCAGCCUGAAGCAGAUCCUGUUGUCUGCAAGUACCCAGCAUCCGAUGGCUUCUCACGGCCUCCACCCCGGCCACCUGGUCCGAGACACUGCUGUCUCCGGCCUGGACUGGUGCAGUAGCCAGCAGCUGCUGCUCUCGCCCUCUAUGGGGCAGCCUCACACGGCCCGUGGUGCCCCUGCUGGUGCUCAGUCCUUGUGCGCUCCCUCCCUUGAGCAUGUGCGGGACCUGUGGUUUAUCUCAAAUGAAUAGAAAAUGGCAAAAGCAAUGGGGUGUCACUUCCAAAUCUGGUCGCGGAAAGACCCUGGUCUAUCUUGCUCAUCCCUCUCACCCUCUCCCACGGUCUGGUGAAACCAGUGGCUGUGCCGAGAGCUGCCAUGGGGCAAGAGACUGAGGGCGGCUUCCAGCUAAACGCCAGUGAGGAGCUGAGGCCCUGAAGAACUGAAUCCCGCCCAGAACUACAUGCCUGAGCUCGGAGCCAUUUCUUCCCCAUGGGAGAUGAGACCCCUGCCCAGCUGAGUCCGGAUUGCAGCCUGUGAGACCCUGAGCCUGCGGAUCCAGCCAAGCCAUACCUGAUCCUUGAUCUAAGGAAAAUGGGAGCUGAUAAGUGUGUGCUGUUUUCAGCUGCCAAGUGUGGGACCCUUUGUGAUGCUGGAGUCAGUAGAUGCCGCAGGCUCACCCCGCCCUCUCCUCCCAGCCAGCAUGAUUAUGUCAAGACCAGAUCAGCUCACAGCACUUCCCUGCUCAUGGCUCCUAGUGUCUCAACAGCCCCAGGCCCUGCCCCAUUUGUCACCUCCCAGCCACCCACCCCAGGCCCUGCACUGUUCGUCACCCCCUGGCCACUGCCUGCUCCCCAGGCCUGCCCUGUUCAUCACCCCCCCAACAGGCCUUGAACCAUUCAUCACCCCCCGGCCACCAGCCCCAGGCCCCGCCCCGUUCGUCACCCCCCCCCGCCACCCACCCCAGGCCCCGCCCCGUUCAUCACCCCCCCACCGGCCACCCGCCCCAGGCCCUGCUCCGUUCGUCACCCCCCGGCCACCCGCCCCAGGCCCCGCCCCGUUCGUCACCCCCUGGCCACCGCCUGCUCUUUCCUUGCUUCCUGGCCUUGAGCCACAUGGGGCAGUUUCCUGAACAUUCCCACUGUGUUUGCACAGGAGGUUCCCUCUGCCUGAGAUGCUGCUCCCUCACGCCUUCCAACAUCAGCUUCUCAGUGAGCCCCUCCCUGAUCUCUCUGCUUAGCCUCAGAUUCCUCCCGUGUCCCUGCCGCUCCUGCUUAUUUGUCUCUGCAGGAUUCAUCAGCAUCGGGCCCUUCCAGCUGUCAACCUACCCCCGCUGCCACUGGGACGCACACUCCACAAAAGCAGGGUUCUCCUGUGUCUUCUCUCUCCCCUGCAGCACCCCCAGGGCCUAGAGCAGUGUCUGACACACGGUGGAGUCUCAGCAAACAUUUGUUCAAGGAGUAAACCGCAGGAGUGGAGGGCAAAUCCAAGCGUGAGCCUGAGCCUGCGUUGCUGCGGGAAUGUGAGCAGGUGCCCCGGUCCACCCCGGCAGAGGCCUCCCCCGCCCAGCGCGUUUCGCCACAUCUCCUCUGGCCAACUGAGUCCUCGCAGAAAGGUGUGUCAAACAGAUCAUUCCUCCACCUGCAUCCCUGAGUGAGGACAAACAGCAGGUCCCCUGAGGACGUGUGAGAGCAGUUGCCUGAGUGAGAGAUACGCCUUCGCCAUUGAAGGCACUGAGUCUGGGGACUGUUUGUUAGAGCAGCAGAACCAAGCAAUCCUGACAGCGCAGAAACCAGCUCCAAGAAAUGAGGUGCUGCCGCAGCCACAGGGCACCUGGAGCACGUGUCCUGCUCACGUGGAGGACAGAGAGAAGGCGGGGCAGAGGCCGGAGCACACUCGGUGUGGAACACUCGGUCAGACUGGACUCGGCAACUUGGAAGUUGGACCAUGAACCUGACGAAACCGCAGCUCUAGGGAAAGGCUGGAAAAUCGCACGUCGGCAGACAUGCCAGUGAGAUCUUUUGAGGAGCCAGACCCAGACAGGAAUUGUCCAUCCUGCCAGCAGGCGUGAAAGUGAACAAGGAGAUUUCAAAAUAUGACACUCCCAGAAAGCUGGAAGAGCCGGCUGACUGUAGACUCCAAGUGAUCAAGAAAGUGCACUGACAAAAGUCUCAAGCAGGGCACGGCGUCACAGCCUUGUUCAUCUCCCGUGCAUCGAGGCGUCUCAUGGUGAAGGUGCCAUGUGGGCAUGGUGAUUUUCACUUGGACAAAACGGCGCAGGGGAAAGUGACCAGGUAGGGAGAGGAGGAUGACGUCCCUGAAACUCAGCUGAGCCAUCGGCAUGGGCGGAAGGCUUUGUGGCCCUGGGAAGGUCGAUGGCGGAGGAGCUGCAGGGGUGGCUGCUGCAUGUGGAGCUGGCUGAAGCCAGAGAUGAGAAAGCUCCUGGGGUCUCGAGAGAGUCGCGAUGACAGGAUGGCACCCACUCAGUCUACAAGAGAAACGUGUGCGUUAAUGCAAACCACCACUAACUCCUGCGACCAGGAGGUGGGCGGCGAAGACUCACCGGCCCCAAGGAAGGCGUGUCCUGGGUACCCACCUCGUACUGGCCGAGAAGGGUCAUGGAGGAAUCAGAAACCUCUCGGAGGGCAGAGCCAGGGGCCUCGGAGGAUGGCAGAAAGGGAGGUGACCUUCAGGUAGGAACUGAAUCUGGACUGAGUGAGGGAGCGUGGACCAGCACCAGGGUGGGUGCUCAGGGGCCUUCCCGGGGGUUUCAGGUCCUCUGUGGACCAGCGACUGCCGCCAUCUCCCUUCUCUCUCUCCCUGCUGCUGGGGCCAUCAUGUCCAUUCCCUGCCACCCACUGUGCACCGAGCAUGAGGGAGGCAAUGACCAAUCUCUUCAGUCUGUGAGUCUCCGGUGAAGAGGUGUCUGGGGUCACCCAGACCCGAUAUGGCUGUGAUUUGGGGUCGUCUCACCUGGGGAGCCAUGACGGGGAGUGAACACAGUCGAUUAGUCCAGAAGGCAGACGUGGAAGUCAGUGGCGCCGCCCACUAAUAUUUUGGCCUCCUUUUCCAGACGCAUUUAGGAUUAUGCUUUCCCUCUCUCUCCAAGUUAGGCCCGGCCAUGUGACCUGCUUUGGCCAAUGAAAUUCUAGCCUUUAAACACGAGUUCAUGAUGCUUCCUGCUUUGGGGAUUGUGGAUGUGUGUUGACACCUGGGUCCCUGUCCCCCAGUGAUGACAAAGAGCAAAGGCACCUGCUGGCCCACGCUGGACACACAUGUGAGAAAGACAUGCAUCUGUGAAGUGCUCAGCUGCUGUGGUGUGGGGCUGUUUGUUACACAGCCCAGCCAAGCCCAGCCUGACUGAUACACUCCCUCAAGCAUGAAUAGGGCUCUGCCUCUCCAAUGAGGGGAGUGGGGCCCAGGGCUGUUUCUCAGCGAUGUCCAGAACACCUUACUCCUAGGUCCCCCAGAAGCAAUGACAAGAAACACCACAGGAGGCAUCUGUGGAGGAGCUGGUCGUGGCAGGGUGGGCACAGCUCUGCCCUGCUGUGGAAGGAGUUGACGAUCCCCCAGGGCCCUGUCCCCGAGGGAGGGCCUGGUCUCCUGAGCAGUGUCCUGGAUCGGGGCUGGCGUGUGAGUAAAAGUGGGUCCAGCCCUCCCCACCCCAAGCUGGGAGAGGUGAGACCCCCACAGCCCACUAGGCGCCAGUGACUGAUGGGCCCGCCACUGUCUUCACAGCCCCCAGAGUUCUCUGGUAAUCACAGGCGUGGAACAUGUGCCAGGAACCUUUGGUUUGCGUGUACCUUUAGAUGCUCGGAUUAAAUUACACCCAUAAUGCA